AGUCGGAGCCUAGCUGCGCGAGAGUUUCUGCUCGCUCAACCGAGUUGUCGUGUUGCCCUCGCUUCUCAGAUCCCCGCCGGAAGUGUAAGUAAGAAACUUCUCUCCUCUUUUCUCACAAUGUGCGCUCACCUAGACGGCCGGGCAGUUAGGAUCGUCUAUUGGAUGUGAAACCAGAGAUGCCCGCCAACCUGGAAUAGAGAGGAAGAGAGCAAGCAGAUUUGAACCUAUCUGCUUUCAAGCUGGUCAUCAUGAUGAAACUUAGACACAAAAAUAAAAAGCCAGGUGAAGGUUCCAAGGGCCACAAGAAGAUAAGUUGGCCCUACCCUCAGCCUGCAAAGCAAAAUGGGAAGAAAGCAACCUCCAAAGUGCCCUCUGCACCUCAUUUUGUUCACCCCAAUGAUCAUGCCAAUCGAGAGGCUGAAUUAAAGAAGAAGUGGGUUGAGGAGAUGAGGGAGAAGCAGCAAGCCGCCCGGGAGCAAGAAAGACAAAAACGCAGGACCAUUGAGAGCUACUGUCAGGAUGUCCUAAGACGCCAGGAGGAGUUUGAGCAUAAGGAGGAAGUUUUGCAGGAAUUAAAUAUGUUUCCUCAGCUGGAUGACGAGGCCACGAGGAAGGCUUAUUACAAGGAGUUCCGUAAGGUGGUGGAAUACUCUGAUGUGAUUCUGGAAGUCCUGGAUGCCAGAGACCCAUUAGGCUGCCGCUGCUUCCAAAUGGAGGAGGCUGUCCUGCGAGCACAAGGCAACAAGAAGCUGGUCCUGGUCUUGAACAAGAUUGACCUGGUCCCCAAGGAGGUUGUGGAGAAAUGGCUGGAUUACCUUCGGAAUGAGUUGCCAACCGUGGCUUUCAAGGCCAGUACCCAGCAUCAGGUCAAAAACCUGAAUCGUUGCAGUGUGCCAGUAGAUCAGGCCUCUGAGUCACUGCUGAAAAGCAAAGCCUGCUUUGGAGCUGAAAACCUCAUGAGGGUUCUGGGGAACUAUUGCCGCCUUGGUGAAGUGCGCACCCACAUUCGUGUGGGUGUUGUGGGUCUUCCCAAUGUUGGGAAGAGCAGCCUGAUCAAUAGCCUGAAGCGCAGCCGCGCAUGCAGCGUGGGAGCUGUUCCUGGAAUUACCAAAUUCAUGCAGGAGGUCUACCUGGACAAGUUCAUCCGGCUCUUGGAUGCUCCAGGCAUUGUCCCAGGGCCCAACUCAGAGGUGGGCACCAUCCUGCGUAACUGCGUCCACGUGCAGAAGCUGGCAGACCCUGUGACCCCAGUGGAGACCAUCCUGCAGCGCUGCAACCUGGAGGAGAUUUCCAACUAUUAUGGCGUCUCUGGGUUCCAGACCACUGAGCACUUUCUGACGGCAGUGGCCCACCGUUUGGGGAAGAAGAAGAAGGGAGGCUUAUAUAGUCAGGAACAGGCGGCCAAAGCUGUCCUAGCUGACUGGGUGAGCGGGAAGAUCAGCUUCUAUAUACCACCACCAGCCACUCACACUCUGCCCACCCAUCUCAGUGCUGAGAUCGUUAAGGAAAUGACCGAGGUCUUUGACAUCGAGGAUACUGAGCAGGCCAAUGAAGACACCAUGGAAUGCUUGGCCACCGGAGAAUCUGAUGAGCUGUUGGGUGACACGGACCCACUUGAAAUGGAGAUCAAGUUGCUCCAUUCUCCGAUGACGAAAAUAGCAGAUGCCAUUGAAAAUAAAACCACCGUGUAUAAGAUUGGAGAUCUCACUGGGUAUUGCACCAAUCCGAACCGUCAUCAGAUGGGGUGGGCUAAACGCAAUGUGGACCACCGCCCUAAGAGCAACAGUAUGGUGGAUGUCUGCUCAGUGGACCGCCGCUCAGUGCUGCAGAGGAUCAUGGAGACGGACCCCCUGCAACAGGGCCAGGCUCUGGCAUCUGCCCUGAAAAAUAAGAAGAAGAUGCAGAAACGUGCAGAUAAAAUCGCCAGCAAGCUGUCUGAUUCCAUGAUGUCUGCUCUCGACCUCUCUGGCAAUGCUGAUGAUGGUGUUGGUGACUAAUCGACUGAUCUCACUUCCCUUCCGCUCCAAGCACCAGUUCCGGUGGUACGGGGGAAUACCAGUGAAAUAGUUUGGUUCUCCCUGAAGCAUCUGCAUAUUGAAAGAACGCUUUCCCCACUGUGUGUCUUCUCCCCCUCCUCCAGUAAAAACAGUCCCGGCUAGGUGCUGUGGCUCACGUCUGUAAUCCCAGCACUUUGGGAGGCCGAGGUGGGCAGAUCACCUGAGGUCAGGAGUUCGAGACCAGCCUGGCCAACAUGGUGAAACCCCGUCUCUACUAAAAAUACAAAAAAAUUUAGCCGUGCUUAGUGGCACCUAUAAUCCCAGCUACUUGGGAGGCUGAGGCAGGAGAAUCGCCUGAACCUGGGAGACUAAGGCAGGAGAAUCGCCUGAACCUGGGAGGCAGAGGUUGCAGUGAGCCCAGACGGCACCAUUGCACUCUAGCCUGGGCAACAACACGAAACUCCGUCCCAAAAAAAAAAAAAAAAAAAAAAUCCCAAGGGGCUGCAGCUGCCAAACCCAAUACCCUCUAUUUAACCCCUACUCUGUUUUACAAGAGAAAUAAAAGAAGUAUCAGCAGAGCUCAGGUGCUAACACCUGUUGAGGGCUGACCUACAAAACUCUGCCUACAAAACUCUCUUAGACAGGUGAAUAUGCCACUAGAAGUUAGGUUGCUGGUAGACCUGGGGGUCCCUGCGGGAGGGUGAUGGUUUCUUUACCACCCCACAGGAGAUUUCAGUGGCAAGGCAUGCCUGCAGUGGGCUUUGGGCCAUGCAUCUUCCAAGUCCAUAGGUCUUCACCUGGGUGGCAGUGAGAAAAAGUAGAAAGUAAUGAGCCUCCUGUGUCUCUGGAAGGUUCUAGGGAUAGGGUAGAGGGAAGAAGAGAACAAACAAGCCUGGCUUGUGCUGAAGUGUGGUAGGCACUACCCUGUUUGCGUGAAGAGAAAACAAAGCACCUGUUAGUAGGGAGGCUUUAGGGGGAAGCCCCGUCUUGGGGGCAUUUCUGGGCAGAUUGUGAAUUGGAGGAAUCUCUUUAACUGAAGUACUCUGGCUGGACCCUGCCCUUGUGUGACCAUGUCUCCUAUUGCACCAGCAUUUGAAUUCCAUGGCUCAAGAGGGUUCUGGUACCAUUUAUUCACAGACUGUAUCCUCGAGAGAGCUGCUAUAUAUGGGAGUGUACCAGCCAACUCCUUUUCCAGUGUCUGUAAGUCACCUCAUUAAAGUAUAAUUAGCUGUCUCCUCUGGGAGAUCCUACCCCAUCAGACAAGGGCAGUGAGCCCAAGCAGUGCCAGAGGCCCUCAGAAAGGGAUUAGGGUAGAUGAUUGCAACUGAAACACAAUCUUCUUUCUUUGCCAGGGUAUUUUGGGGGUUUUGCCCCAAAAUAUACCCUGGGCAUAGCAUUACUGCAGUCUUGGAUGUCUACCCCAAACUUCCACACCAUCCUUCGACCCACAGCUGCACCUUUAUUUAUUUAUUUUGCUCUGUUGCCCAGGCUGGAGUGCAAUGGCGUGAUCUCGGCUCACUGCAACCUCUGCCUCCCGGGUUCAAGUGAUCCUCCUGCCUUAGCCUCCCAAGUAGCUGGGAUUACAGGCACCUGCCACCACGCCUGGCUAGUUUUUGUAUUUUUAGUAGAGACGAUGUUUCACCAUGUUGACCAGGCUGGUCUCGAACUCUUGACCUCAAGUGAUCCACUCGCUUCGGCCUCCCAAAGUGCUGGGAUUAUAGGCGUGAGCCACUGUGCCCAGCCUCACAGCUGCAUCUUAACCUUACCUUUGCCUCUGCCUCUCAAGCUGGUACCUCCUAAUUUACAUCCUAAGAGUGGAACCAUGUGACAAGGACUGGAGUGCCAUUGGCUGUGGACUGUUCAGGCAGGGAAGUACAAGACCACUCUUGUAUUCAGGGGCAACCAAAGGAGAGAAUUACGUACUUGUUGAGUACAAACUGCACCAAGCCCUGGAGACCCAUUACCACCGUUAACCCUCAAUACAGCUCUGCUAGUAAGGGAUUCGUCUCCCCAAAUGAAAAAAAAAAGUAAUCUCAGAAUGUUGGCCGAGCAUGGUGGCUCACACCUGUAAUCCCAGUUAUGCAGGAGGCUGAGGCAGGAGAAUCACUUGAUCUCAGGAGGCGGAGGUUGCAGUGAGUCGACAUCACACCACUGCACUCCAGCCUGGGGGACAGAGUGAGACUUCGUCUCGGAAAAAAAAAAAAAAAGUUGACAGGAUGGCCAGACCCAAGUGGGCGUAUUAAGUGGUGGUGCUAGGAUUGGAACCCAAGCGUGAUUAAAACCCUAUGCAGGCCCUUUCCUCUAUAUUGUACUGCCUCCUUAACAAAGGAAGAUUGAUUAAGCCCCUACUUUGUGCCAGUCUCUGUUAUCAAGUCCGUUAAAUGCAUUUAACGUUAAAUUUUUUCUUUUUUGGUUUAAAAAACUCUAGUUUCUUAAACUACUAGUUUUUAGUGUCUUGCUAAAACUAUGUGCUCUUGAAUAGGCUACAACUUAUUUCACACUAUCUCAUUGAACUCUCCUGGUAUGUGAUAGUGUUAUAAUGAAAAAUUGCAUACCAGGACAGCUAAGUCUAUUUUGCAACCAUACAGCGUUUCAUAAUUUAGCAUUUAAAAUACAGACAGUCCCCGACUUUUGGUGGUUUGAUGUGGGAUUUUUGGUGGAAAAGCAGUAUACAUUCAGAAUGCACCUCUACUUAUGAUGGGGCUACUUCCUGGUAAACCCAUUGUAAUGUGCAAAUUACGGGUUUAUCAGGAGGUGACCCCAUCGGUAAUGGAGAAGUGCUGGGAGGUAAAUAUUAGAAAUGGAAGUAUCUAAAUGAGUAAGAAACAGCAUGGGAGCAUAAUUUGGCCAAAAUCAAACAGAACUAAAGUAGUCAUGUCGGUAAGAAUUUGGGACUGCAGGCCAGUUACGAUAGCUCUCACCUGUAAUCCCAGCAUUUUGGGAGGCCGAGGCAGGCGGAUCACUUGAGGUCAGGAGUUCAAGACCAGCCUAAACAAUAUGGCGAAACCUCAUCUCUACCAAAAAAAUACAAAGAUUAGCUGGGCAUGGUGUCUCAUGCCUGUAGUCCCAGCUACCUAUGGGGCUGAGGCAGGAGGAUCUCUUGAGCCCAGGAGGUCGAUGCUGCAUUGAGCCGAGAUUGUGCCACUGCUCUCCAGCGUGGGCAACAGAGUGAGACUGUCUCAGGGGGAAAAAAAAAGAGGAAAACAAAAAAGACGUUGGGAGUGCAGUUUCUCUACCUACAGCAUAUCUCAAAGGUUUUUUUUAAAAAAGUAUUUUCUUAACUUUUUACCUUCAUUUUUCAAAACAAUUAGGGUACAAUUUACAUAUAGUAAAGUUCACUCUUUAUAGUUUUAGUUAUGUGAGUUUGUACAAACAUAUACAGGAGUGAACCACUACCACAAUCGAAAUAUAGUUGCAUCACCCCCCUAAAACUCUCCAGGCCCUUUUGUAGUCAACUCCUACCCCCGACCCUCAGAUUCUGCUAACCACUGAUUUGUUUUCUGCCCCUAUAGUUUUGCUUUAGUAUGACUGUCAUAUCAAUAGAAUCAUACAAUGAGUAGGCUUAUUUUAUGCCUUCAGGUUUUAAAAAUUAUAAACAUUUACAUUACAGUAAAAUUCACUCUGGUAUACAGUUCUAUAAAGCUCUGAUAAAUGUGUAGAGUUGUGUAACCACCAAUGCAACCAAGGUACAGAACAGUCCUCUUAGCCUCUCCCUACCAAAUUUAUUCCUGCUACUUUGUAGUCAAAACCAGUCCCCUACACCCAAACCCUGGCAGUCACUGGUUUUUUUCUUCGUUCUCUUUUUUUUUUUUUUUUUUUUGAGACAGAGUCUAGCUCUGUUGUCCAGGCUGGAGUGGUGCAGUGGCGUGAUCUCGGUUCACUGCAACCUCCGCCUCCAGGGUUCAAGCGGUUCUCCUGCCUCAGCCUCCCGAGUAGCUGGGAUUAUGGGCGCCCGCCACCACGCCCAGCUAAUUUUUGUAUUUUUAGUAGAGAUGGGGUUUCACUGUUUUGGCCAGGCUGGUCUCGAACUCCUGACCUCAUGAUCCUCCUGCCUCAGCCUCCCAAAGUGCUGGGAUUACAAGAGUGAGCCACUGCGCCUGGCCUUUUUCUUUGUUCUUAUAUUUUUGUCUUUUUUUUUUUUUUUUUUUUGAAACAGAGUCUCACUCUUUCACUGAGGCUGGAGUGCAGUGGCGUGAUCUUGGCUCACUGCAACCUCCACCUCCUGGGUUCAAGCGAUUCUCCUGCCUUAGCCUCCCGAGUAACAGGGACUACAGGUGCCCACCACCAUGCUGGGCUAAUUUUUGUAUUUUUAGUAGAGGCGGGGGUUUCUCCACACUGGCCAGGCUGGUCUUGAACUUCUGACCUCAAAAGAUCCACCCACCUCGGCCUCCCAAAGUGCUGGGAUUAUAGGCAUGAACCACCGUGUCCGGCCAUAUAUUUUCGUCUUUUGAAGACUGUUAUAUACAUGAAAUUAUAUGGUAUGUAGCAUUUUGAGAGCGACUUCUUUUGCUAUGAGUAAUACAUUUGAGAUUCAUCCAUAUUUCUCAGUAUAUUAAUAGUUCUUAUUUCUGAGUCACUCCAUUGUGUGGAUUUACUACUGUUUGUUCCCCAGUUGAAGGAUGUUUAGGAUCUUUGCAGUUUUGGACAAUUACAAGUAAAGCUGCUAUAAACAUUUGUAUGCAACAUUUUGUGUUUUCAUUUAUCUAUAGUAAAUACCUAGAGUUGGAUUGCUGGGAUAUAUGGUAAGCAUAUGUUUGACAUUUUAAGAAACUUCUAAACUGUUUUUCAAAGUGGCUCUACCAUUUCACAUUCCCAUCAGUAUGAAAGUUUCAUUUCCACAUCCUCUCUAGUACUUGGGGGUGUCAGUUUAGUUUUUUAAUUUUUAAAUUUUUUAAUUUUUUUAAUACAUUUAAAUAGAGAUGGGGUCUCACUGUGUUGACCAGGAUGGUCUUGAACUGCUGGCCUCAAGUAAUCCUCCCAUCUCGGUCUCCCAAAGUGCUAGGAUUACAGGUGUGAGCCACCAUGCCCAGCCAGGUUUUUUGACAUUAAGUAUGUGGUGGUAUCUCAUCGUUUUUAUUUGCAUCCUCUAAUGAUUUGAGCAUAUUUUAUAUGCUUAUUUGCUAUCUACAUAUCUUCUUUGGCAAGGUGUUCACAUCUCUUGCAUAUUUUGGAUUGUUUUAUUAUUUUUGAAUUUUGAGGAUUAUAUGCUGGAUACAGGGGUGUUUUUUUUUUUUUUUUUUUUUGAAACAGAGUCCUCACCCAGGUUGGAGUGUAGUGGUGCAAUCUCGGCUCACUGCAACCUCUGCCUCCUGGGUUCAAGUAAUUCUCAUGCCUCAGCCUCCUGAGUAGCUGGAAUUACAGGCGCAGGCCACCAUGCUUGGCUAACUUUUAUAUUUUUACCAGAGACAAGGUUUCACCAUGUUGGCAAGGCUGGUCUUGAACUCUGGACCUCAAGUGAUACACCCGUCUUAGCCUCCCAAAGUUCUGGGAUUACAGGCAUGAGCCAUUGUGCCUGGCCAGUAUCUUGUCUUCUCAUUCUGUAAACGGUGUCUUUUUUUCAUUAUGGGAAAGCUUUAUUGACACAUUUGUUUUUAUUUUUAAAAAUUAUGGUAAAAUACACAGAACAUAAACGUUACCAUCUGAUAUGGUUUGGCUGUGUCCACACCUAAAUCUCGAAUUGUAGUUCCCAUAAUCCCCACACAUAUGUACCACAUUUUCUUUAUCCAGUCUUUCGUUGAUAGACAUUUAGGUCGAUUCCAUGUCUUUGGUAUUGUGAAUAGUGCUGCAGUGAACAUAUGUGUGCAUGUGUCUUUAUGGCAGAAUGAUUUAUAUUAUGCAUAACCAAAACUGUACUUAUUAAACAAUAACCUCCCAACCCCUUCUGCCCACAACCUCUGGCGACUGCCAUGCUACUUUCUGUCUCUGAAUUUGAAUACCCUGAUAGUCAUAUAAUAUUUAUCUUUUUGUGACUGGCUUAUUUCACUUUGCAUAAUGUAUUCAAGCUUAAUCUGUGUUGUAGCCUGCGUCAGAAUUUCUUUUCUUUUUAAUGCUGAGUAUUAUUCUAUUGUGUGUAUAUACCACAUUUUAUUUAUCCAUUCAUCCACUGAUGGACAUGUGCAUUGUUCCCACCUUUUGGCUAUUGUGAAAAAUGCUGUUAUGAAUAUGGGUAUGGAGAUCUCUCCCCUUAUUUUGAGACAGGAUCUCACUGUCACCCAGGCUGGGGUGCAGUGGUGUGCUCAUAGGUCACUGUAGCUUCGACCUCCUGGGCUCAAGCGAACCUCCCACCUCCGCCUCUUGAGUAGCUGGGACCACAGGCAUGUGCCACCAUGGCUGUUAAAUUUAUUAAUUUGUUUUUCUAUGGAUCAUGCUUUUUGUGUUACAUCAGAGGAGUCUUUGCUUAACAUGAGAUGACAAAGGUUUUCUCCCAUGUUUCCUCCUAAAAGUUUUAUAGUUUUAGGUUUUACAUUUAGGUCUAUGAUCCAUUUUGAGUCAAUUUUUGUAUAUGGUACAAGGUAUGAAUCUAUGCUUUUUAAAAAAAUAUGGUUACCCAAUUUUUCUAGCAGUAUGUGCUAAAACUUUGCUAAAGUCACUUAGUUCUAGUAGCUUUUUUUGCAGAUUUAACCAGACUUUCUACAUAGACAAUCAUAUCUUCUGUGAAUAAACAUGGUUUUAUUUCUUCAUGUCUAA